GACUAUAAAGUCCCCAUCCGGACUCAAGAAGUUCUCAGGACUCAGAGGCUGGGAUCAUGGUAGAUGGAACCCUCCUUUUACUCCUCUCGGAGGCCCUGGCCCUUACCCAGACCUGGGCGGGUGAGUGCGGGGUCGGGAUGGAAACGGCCUCUACCGGGAGUAGAGAGGGGCCGGCCCGGCGGGGGCGAAGGACUCGGGGAGCCGCGCCGGGAGGAGGGUCGGGCCGAUCUCAGCCCCUCCUCGCCCCCAGGCUCCCACUCCUUGAAGUAUUUCCACACUUCCGUGUCCCGGCCCGGCCGCGGGGAGCCCCGCUUCAUCUCUGUGGGCUACGUGGACGACACCCAGUUCGUGCGCUUCGACAACGACGCCGCGAGUCCGAGGAUGGUGCCGCGGGCGCCGUGGAUGGAGCAGGAGGGGUCAGAGUAUUGGGACCGGGAGACACGGAGCGCCAGGGACACCGCACAGAUUUUCCGAGUGAACCUGCGGACGCUGCGCGGCUACUACAAUCAGAGCGAGGCCGGGUCUCACACCCUGCAGUGGAUGCAUGGCUGCGAGCUGGGGCCCGACAGGCGCUUCCUCCGCGGGUAUGAACAGUUCGCCUACGACGGCAAGGAUUAUCUCACCCUGAAUGAGGACCUGCGCUCCUGGACCGCGGUGGACACGGCGGCUCAGAUCUCCGAGCAAAAGUCAAAUGAUGCCUCUGAGGCGGAGCACCAGAGAGCCUACCUGGAAGACACAUGCGUGGAGUGGCUCCACAAAUACCUGGAGAAGGGGAAGGAGACGCUGCUUCACCUGGAGCCCCCAAAGACACACGUGACUCACCACCCCAUCUCUGACCAUGAGGCCACCCUGAGGUGCUGGGCCCUGGGCUUCUACCCUGCGGAGAUCACACUGACCUGGCAGCAGGAUGGGGAGGGCCAUACCCAGGACACGGAGCUCGUGGAGACCAGGCCUGCAGGGGAUGGAACCUUCCAGAAGUGGGCAGCUGUGGUGGUGCCUUCUGGAGAGGAGCAGAGAUACACGUGCCAUGUGCAGCAUGAGGGGCUACCCGAGCCCGUCACCCUGAGAUGGAAGCCGGCUUCCCAGCCCACCAUCCCCAUCGUGGGCAUCAUUGCUGGCCUGGUUCUCCUUGGAUCUGUGGUCUCUGGAGCUGUGGUUGCUGCUGUGAUAUGGAGGAAGAAGAGCUCAGGUGGAAAAGGAGGGAGCUACUCUAAGGCUGAGUGGAGCGACAGUGCCCAGGGGUCUGAGUCUCACAGCUUGUAAAGCCUGAGACAGCUGCCUUGUGUGCGACUGAGAUGCACAGCUGCCUUGUGUGCGACUGAGAUGCAGGAUUUCCUCACGCCUCCCCUAUGUGUCUUAGGGGACUCUGGCUUCUCUUUUUGCAAGGGCCUCUGAAUCUGUCUGUGUCCCUGUUAGCACAAUGUGAGGAGGUAGAGAAACAGUCCACCUCUGUGUCUACCAUGACCCCCUUCCUCACACUGACCUGUGUUCCUUCCCUGUUCUCUUUUCUAUUAAAAAUAAGAACCUGGGCAGAGUGCGGCAGCUCAUGCCUGUAAUCCCAGCACUUAGGGAGGCCGAGGAGGGCAGAUCACGAGGUCAGGAGAUCGAAACCAUCCUGGCUAACACGGUGAAACCCCGUCUCUACUAAAAAAUACAAAAAAUUAGCUGGGCGCAGAGGCACGGGCCUGUAGUCCCAGCUACUCAGGAGGCGGAGGCAGGAGAAUGGCGUCAACCCGGGAGGCGGAGGUUGCAGUGAGCCAGGAUUGUGCGACUGCACUCCAGCCUGGGUGACAGGGUGAAACGCCAUCUCAAAAAAUAAAAAUUAAAAAAUAAAAAAAGAACCUGGAUCUCAAUUUAAUUUUUCAUAUUCUUGCAAUGAAAUGGACUUGAGGAAGCUAAGAUCAUAGCUAGAAAUACAGAUAAUUCCACAGCACAUCUCUAGCAAAUUUAGCCUAUUCCUAUUCUCUAGCCUAUUCCUUACCACCUGUAAUCUUGACCAUAUACCUUGGAGUUGAAUAUUGUUUUCAUACUGCUGUGGUUUGAAUGUUCCCUCCAACACUCAUGUUGAGACUUAAUCCCUAAUGUGGCAAUACUGAAAGGUGGGGCCUUUGAGAUGUGAUUGGAUCGUAAGGCUGUGCCUUCAUUCAUGGGUUAAUGGAUUAAUGGGUUAUCACAGGAAUGGGACUGGUGGCUUUAUAAGAAGAGGAAAAGAGAACUGAGCUAGCAUGCCCAGCCCACAGAGAGCCUCCACUAGAGUGAUGCUAAGUGGAAAUGUGAGGUGCAGCUGCCACAGAGGGCCCCCACCAGGGAAAUGUCUAGUGUCUAGUGGAUCCAGGCCACAGGAGAGAGUGCCUUGUGGAGCGCUGGGAGCAGGACCUGACCACCACCAGGACCCCAGAACUGUGGAGUCAGUGGCAGCAUGCAGCGCCCCCUUGGGAAAGCUUUAGGCACCAGCCUGCAACCCAUUCGAGCAGCCACGUAGGCUGCACCCAGCAAAGCCACAGGCACGGGGCUACCUGAGGCCUUGGGGGCCCAAUCCCUGCUCCAGUGUGUCCGUGAGGCAGCACACGAAGUCAAAAGAGAUUAUUCUCUUCCCACAGAUACCUUUUCUCUCCCAUGACCCUUUAACAGCAUCUGCUUCAUUCCCCUCACCUUCCCAGGCUGAUCUGAGGUAAACUUUGAAGUAAAAUAAAAGCUGUGUUUGAGCAUCA